GCCCUGUUCGCCCCGCGCCACCGGCCCGCGCCCCGCCAUGGAGGACCUGGAUGCCCUGCUCUCUGACCUGGAGACUACCACCUCGCACAUGCCAAGGUCAGGGGCUCCCAAAGAGCGCCCUGCGGAGCCUCUCACCCCUCCCCCAUCCUAUGGCCACCAGCCACAGACAGGGUCUGGGGAGUCUUCAGGAGCCUCGGGGGACAAGGACCACCUGUACAGCACGGUAUGCAAGCCUCGGUCCCCAAAGCCUGCAGCCCCGGCGGCCCCUCCAUUCUCCUCUUCCAGCGGUGUCUUGGGUACCGGGCUCUGUGAGCUAGAUCGGUUGCUUCAGGAACUUAAUGCCACUCAGUUCAACAUCACAGAUGAAAUCAUGUCUCAGUUCCCAUCUAGCAAGGUGGCUUCAGGAGAGCAGAAGGAGGACCAGUCUGAAGAUAAGAAAAGACCCAGCCUCCCUUCCAGCCCGUCUCCUGGCCUCCCAAAGGCUUCUGCCACCUCAGCCACUCUGGAGCUGGAUAGACUGAUGGCCUCACUCUCUGACUUCCGCGUUCAAAACCAUCUUCCAGCCUCUGGGCCAACUCAGCCACCGGUGGUGAGCUCCACAAAUGAGGGCUCCCCAUCCCCACCAGAGCCGACUGGCAAGGGCAGCCUAGACACCAUGCUGGGGCUGCUGCAGUCCGACCUCAGCCGCCGGGGUGUUCCCACCCAGGCCAAAGGCCUCUGUGGCUCCUGCAAUAAACCUAUUGCUGGGCAAGUGGUGACGGCUCUGGGCCGCGCCUGGCACCCCGAGCACUUCGUUUGCGGAGGCUGUUCCACCGCCCUGGGAGGCAGCAGCUUCUUCGAGAAGGAUGGAGCCCCCUUCUGCCCCGAGUGCUACUUUGAGCGCUUCUCGCCAAGAUGUGGCUUCUGCAACCAGCCCAUCCGACACAAGAUGGUGACCGCCUUGGGCACUCACUGGCACCCAGAGCAUUUCUGCUGCGUCAGUUGCGGGGAGCCCUUCGGAGAUGAGGGUUUCCACGAGCGCGAGGGCCGCCCCUACUGCCGCCGGGACUUCCUGCAGCUGUUCGCCCCGCGCUGCCAGGGCUGCCAGGGCCCCAUCCUGGAUAACUACAUCUCGGCGCUCAGCGCGCUCUGGCACCCGGACUGUUUCGUCUGCAGGGAAUGCUUCGCGCCCUUCUCGGGAGGCAGCUUUUUCGAGCACGAGGGCCGCCCGUUGUGCGAGAACCACUUCCACGCACGACGCGGCUCGCUGUGCGCCACGUGUGGCCUCCCUGUGACCGGCCGCUGCGUGUCGGCCCUGGGUCGCCGCUUCCACCCGGACCACUUCACAUGCACCUUCUGCCUGCGCCCGCUCACCAAGGGGUCCUUCCAGGAGCGCGCCGGCAAGCCCUACUGCCAGCCCUGCUUCCUGAAGCUCUUCGGCUGACAGCCCGCUCGGCUCGCCCUCUCCCCCGGAGGCCGCGCCCUCCCGGAAAAGCCGGGUCCUCCAGACCCCGAGGCCUUGCUCUCAGAGCGGGAGGCCCCACCCACUGGAGAGCCCCGCCCCUAAGGUACUAUGAGUCCUCAGGGGUCAAGUUCAGAAACGGCCCAGCCAGACCUAAACCCACACGCCCACAAAGUGGAUUGCACACAGACAAGAACUCCCGUGCGGGCCUCCACUCUAUUCCCACCCUUGAGGGAGCCCCCUUACUGGGGGAGGGUCCUUGCAAUUCCAGCGAAUCGGAGGCCAGGCCAGGACGUCCUUGCUCCCUGCACCCUCACUGUUCUGUGCACUUUUUCUACCUACAUAAACACACGCAUUCCACCUC